CGAGACUCCAUCUCAAAAACAAAACAAAUAAACGAACAAAAAAACCCACAACGUAUUAUUUUCUUGUUUACGAGGUUUCUUGUCUCUCUGGCUCCACCAGAAGAGGAGCAGGGACCCUUCUUGCUGUUGUUCAUUGCUGCAUCCCCCACACCGAGAGCAGAGCCUGGCAUGGGCAGAAAGUCCUCAGUCGAUAUUUGGUGGCCCCAAGCGAAUGAAGCAUCCAAGAAGGGAAAGCUGGGGGCUCCCCACUGCACUUGCCACCUGAGUCACAUUUUCAGAAGCCUCUGGAAAGUCGUGCACAGCCCAGGAGUGUUGAGCAAUUUCGGUUUCCUCUGAGGUUGAAGGACCCAGGCGUGUCAGCCCUGCUCCAGACACCUUGGGCAUGGAGGAGAGUGUCGUACGGCCCUCAGUGUUUGUGGUGGAUGGACAGACCGACAUCCCAUUCACGAGGCUGGGACGAAGCCACCGGAGACAGUCGUGCAGUGUGGCCCGGGUGGGUCUGGGUCUCUUGCUGUUGCUGAUGGGGGCCGGGCUGGCCGUCCAAGGCUGGUUCCUCCUGCAGCUGCACUGGCGUCUAGGAGAGAUGGUCACCCGCCUGCCUGACGGACCUGCAGGCUCCUGGGAGCAGCUGAUACAAGAGCGAAGGUCUCACGAGGUCAACCCAGCAGCGCAUCUCACAGGGGCCAACUCCAGCUUGACCGGCAGCGGGGGGCCGCUGUUAUGGGAGACUCAGCUGGGCCUGGCCUUCCUGAGGGGCCUCAGCUACCACGAUGGGGCCCUUGUGGUCACCAAAGCUGGCUACUACUACAUCUACUCCAAGGUGCAGCUGGGCGGUGUGGGCUGCCCGCUGGGCCUGGCCAGCACCAUCACCCACGGCCUCUACAAGCGCACACCCCGCUACCCCGAGGAGCUGGAGCUGUUGGUCAGCCAGCAGUCACCCUGCGGACGGGCCACCAGCAGCUCCCGGGUCUGGUGGGACAGCAGCUUCCUGGGUGGUGUGGUACACCUGGAGGCUGGGGAGAAGGUGGUCGUCCGUGUGCUGGAUGAACGCCUGGUUCGACUGCGUGAUGGUACCCGGUCUUACUUCGGGGCUUUCAUGGUGUGAAGGAAGGAGCGUGGUGCAUUGGACAUGGGUCUGACACGUGGAGAACUCAGAGGGUGCCUCAGGGGAAAGAAAACUCACGAAGCAGAGGCUGGGCGUGGUGGCUCUCGCCUGUAAUCCCAGCACUUUGGGAGGCCAAGGCAGGCGGAUCACCUGAGGUCAGGAGUUCGAGACCAGCCUGGCUAACAUGGCAAAACCCCAUCUCUACUAAAAAUACAAAAAUUAGCCGGACGUGGUGGUGCCUGCCUGUAAUCCAGCUACUCAGGAGGCUGAGGCAGGAUAAUUUUGCUUAAACCCGGGAGGCGGAGGUUGCAGUGAGCCGAGAUCACACCACUGCACUCCAACCUGGGAAACGCAGUGAGACUGUGCCUCAAAAAAAAGAAAGGAAGAAAAAAGAAAACUCAGGAAACAGAUCUUGGGGGACACUCCAGGGAACCCAAAACUCAAAGGCGGAGAGCUCAGUGGGCACCACCAAGGCGAGAUGAAGCCCCAGCAGGCACCUUCAGAAGACCCACGUAGACUGCAGACCCUGCCACGGACAAUACUAAGGACAAAAACCCAGAGACUUGGGGUCUGUGGGCCCCCAAACAUGGGGUAAAGUUGAUUUGCCUGAUAUUCAGGAAGAAGGGGUGAGGGGUGGGUAUUUAUGCUUUUGAUUCAGAAGAAAGUGGGGCUUGGGAUUCCAGGGACUUGGCUGGGGGUGGGAAACUUCAUCCACUUCCCUACUCUCAUCAUGAGUACGGACAGGGUGGGCGGGAGACUGAUCAUCGGGACUCAUCAUGAAGAGCCCAGCCCCACCCCACAUACUCAGAUCCCACCCACAGACUGGUGGCCACACCUCAGCCUGGUCACAAAGAGUUACACUCAGAUACAUGAGCACGGCAGCGUGCUCAUAACUGUUUAACAACCAGCUGUCCUGGGAGGGGGACAGCUUUGUAAUGUUUGCCAAUUUCCAUGGUGUAAAUGCUACCACCAUGGCUGAUUUCAUCACUGCCAAGCAUAGACAUCCCUAAUAGGACACCACGGAUCUGUCCCCGGCAUCCGGCCCAGGGCCUGGCACAAAGCAUGCUCUAGGGAAAUGCUUGCUGAUUGAAAGGAAGGAAGAAUGACUCUACAGUCACACCUAUGGCAUCCCACAAAAUCUGUCACAUGGCUGCAUAAUCUCAGCCACUCUUUCACAACUAUAGACUCAUACACGCGAAGUGCCAGAUUCAUGCACAACCACACAAUCACAUGGAAGUCACAGACGGCAUCACAGACAGUCACAGCACUGUGUGUAUGUUAUAACACAAGCACACAAAACUCAGACAGCAUCCCAGCUACACAGCCACUCCCAGAGGUGUCACCGUCACACUUGGUAAUUAAUACUCAUUACAUUAGACACAGACAGACCAAGUUAUAGUCAGACCUGGUUACACACAUACACACACACAAUAUCACCAUGACAAAUACACAUUACACACACACAACAUCACAAUGACAAACACACAUUACACACACAACAUCACGAUGACAAACACACAUUACACACACAACAUCACGAUGACAAACACACAUUACACACACAUCACAAUGACAAACACAACAUUACACACACACAACAUCACAAUGACACACACAUCACACACACAUCACAAUGACAAACACACAACAUUACACACAUAUACACACAGCCUGAGGGCCCUCCCCAGCCCAGACUAACACAUCUCGGGGUGAGGACCAGACCUUGUUCAUAACCCUGGGCCUCUUAACCACUGAUCUUUGAAAUAAAUGGCAAAUAGUUGUACCUGGAUCUGUCUAGUUCUUAGGGGAACAAACUGAAGAAGGGUGGAGAGGAAUUGUCAGGCCUAAAGAGCCCCACAGGGAAAGGGAGGAGUCGGAUGGGGGGCAACCAUCAGCAACAAGUGGUGGCUCCUAGAGGCAGAGGGAUGGAGGUAAUGACCCAUGGAGGUCAUUCUACAGAUGAGGAACCUGGACCCAGUUGGCUCAAGUCCAUGCAGGAAAUGUGGGGGAAACCAGAGACCUCACGUCUGGAUCUGGCUUCCUCUCCAAUCCACAAUUCCUGAGGAAGUAGAGGCUACAUCCCGCAAGACGCCCUUAUUAGACACAUCCAGGACAGAAUGACAAUCCGCCAAGCCAGCUGGAAGCAUAAAACACAGGGAGCUGGUGGGUUGGGUGGGGGCAGAUAAUGAUAUGCAUACAAAUUAGAGGGUCUAUGCAAAUGAGCAUUGCUGCAGUGUGGCUGGAGGGAAUCCUUAGUUCCUAGGAUUCUAGGAUAUGGGUUUCGACCCCAGAGGUGAAUGUAUUGUUAUUAUUGUUUUGUUGUUGUUGUGAAUGACAAGUCAAAAUUUGUGGGUUAUUGUUGUUAUCGCCAAUAGUAUUCUUGUCAUUGUUGCACAGUACAGAGAUGAAGGAAACAGAUUUUGCAAUCAGAUGAUCCUGGGUUCUGAGUCCACUCUGCCACUCACCAGCUAUAUGACCUCCAGCAAUUUCCAUCACCUCUCAAUGCUUCAGUUUCCCCAUCGGCAAGAUGGUUGUGGGGGGAGAGGAACAACAGUACAGAUUCACCAUCCCAAAUUCAAAAUGCUCCAAAAUCUAGGCCGGGCGUGGUGGCUCAUACCUGUAAUCCCAGCACUUUGGGAGGUCAAAGUGGACGGAUAACCUGAGGUCAGGAGCUCCAGACCAGCCUGGCCAACAUGGCGAAACCCCAUCUCUACUAAAAAUACAAAAAAUUACCUGGGUGUGGUGGGGGGCACCUGUAACCCCAGCUACUCGGGAGGCUGAGGCAGGAACCCUGGAGGUUGAGGUUGCAGUGAGCUGAGAUCACACCACUGCACUCCAGCCUGGGUGACAGAGCAAGGCUCCCAUCUCAAAAAACAAAAAAACAUGCUCCAAAAUCUGAAACUCUUUGAGCCCCAGUGUGAUGCCACAAGUGGGAAAUUCCACAACUCAUCACAUGUGAUAGAUUGCAGUGGAAAUGCAGGCACACACCACGAAGUUUACUCAGCAUCCUCAAAGGAAAUCCCCGUCAGUAGCUAUAUAUCAUUUUCUCACAUGCCAGAUAGGUAUCUCUCAUCUUUUACUGUUAGGUACUUCUGUGUUGAAUAGGUGGAGGAAAAUGAUUGCUGGUUAGUAGUAUAUAAAUUCAGAGUCAGGAAGGAUGGUGAUGUCGGCUGGGUGCAGUGGCUCAUGCCUGUAAUUCCAAUGUGAUACCCUACCUUGUGUUUAACGUGAUUGACUCUCCCUUAGCUGAGAGGGCCAGGCAGACUCUAUUUUGGCUUCUUCGCUUGCAGUCUCUCACCCACCCCCCUUCCUCAAGGACUUAAGCUGACUCCCAGCACAUCCAAGAAUGCGAUUACUGAUAAGAUACUGUGACAAGCUAUAUCCACAAUUCCCAGGAAUUCGUCCGGUUGAUAGCACCCAAAGCCCCCGCGUCUAUCACCUUGUGAUAGAUUUAAAGCCCCUGCACCUGGAACUGUUUGUUUUUCUGUUACCAUUUAUCUUUUUCACUUUCUUGCCUGUUUUGCUUCUGUAAAAUUGCUUCAGCUCGGCUCCCUCUUCCCCUUCUAAACCAAGGUAUAAAAAGAAACCUAGCCCCUUCUUUGGGGUGGAGAGAAUUUUGAGCGCUAGCCGUCUCUCAGUCGCCGGCUAAUAAAGGACUCCUGAAUUAGUCUAA